ACAAACGCCGGGGCCUGAGAUCGCGGUGGAUGCACGCGCGGGAGCCUGGCUUGGGAUAAUAAAGUGACGUUGGCUGCUGCAGAAGGAGUUCACCACCUACGACUUCCCCAGCAUGUCUGCUGAAAAUAAUCAGUUAUCAGGAGCAUCACCUCCUCACCCUCCCACAACUCCCCAAUAUUCCACACAGAACUUGCCUUCAGAGAAAGAGGAUACUGAAGUAGAACUAGAUGAGGAAAGUCUACAGGAUGAAUCUCCAUUUUCUCCAGAGGGAGAGUCUCUGGAGGACAAAGAGUAUCUGGAGGAGGAAGAGGAUCUGGAAGAGGAAGAGUAUCUGGGGAAAGAAGAAUACUUGAAGGAGGAAGAGUAUCUGGGGAAGGAAGAGCAUCUGGAGGAGGAAGAGUAUCUGGAGAAGGCAGGGUAUCUGGAGGAGGAAGAGUAUAUUGAAGAGGAAGAGUAUCUGGGGAAGGAAGGGUAUCUGGAGGAGGAAGAGUACCUGGGGAAGGAAGAGCAUCUGGAGGAGGAAGAGUAUCUGGGGAAGGAAGGGUAUCUGGAGAAGGAAGAUUAUAUUGAGGAGGUAGAUUAUCUGGGGAAGAAAGCGUAUCUGGAGGAGGAGGAGUAUCUGGGGAAGAAAUCAUAUCUAGAAGAGGAAAAGGCUCUGGAGAAGGAAGAGAAUCUGGAGGAGGAAGAAGCUCUGGAGAAGGAAGAGAAUCUGGAUGGAAAAGAAAAUCUGUAUAAAAAGUAUCUGAAAGAACCCAAGGCAAGUUAUUCAUCACAAACCAUGCUUCUUCGUGAUGCAAGGAGUCCAGACGCUGGCCCCUCUCAGGUGACCACCUUCUUGACUGUCCCGUUGACUUUCGCUACCCCUUCUCCUGUCUCUGAAUCUGCCACAGAGUCUUCUGAGUUGCUUCUGACAUUGUACAGGAGGAGCCAGGCCAGUCAGACAGACUGGUGCUACGACAGAACUGCCGUAAAAUCUUUAAAAUCGAAAUCAGAAACAGAGCAAGAAACCACCACGAAGCUGGCUCCGGAAGAGCAUGUUAACACUAAAGUACAGCAAAAAAAGGAAGAAAAUGUCCUGGAGUUUGCUUCUAAAGAGAACUUUUGGGAUGGUAUAACAGAUGAGUCCAUUGACAAGCUGGAAGUGGAAGAUUUAGAUGAAAACUUUUUGAACAGCUCCUAUCAGACAGUAUUUAAAACAAUAAUCAAAGAAAUGGCUGCUCACAAUGAACUGGAAGAGGAUUUUGACAUUCCCCUAACUAAGCUACUGGAAAGUGAAAACAGAUGGAAACUGGUAAUUAUGCUGAAGAAAAAUUAUGAAAAGUUCAAGGAAACAAUCUUACGGAUUAAGAGGAGACGUGAAGCUCAAAAGUUAACAGAGAUGACCAGUUUCACAUUUCAUUUAAUGAGCAAACCAACACCUGAGAAGCCUGAGACAGAAGAAAUCCAAAAGCCUCAACGUGUUGUUCAUCAUAGGAAGAAAUUAGAACGAGAUAAGGAAUGGAUACAGAAGAAGACAGUGGUGCAUCAAGGUGAUGGAAAAUUAAUUCUCUACCCCAACAAGAAUGUCUAUCAAAUUCUCUUUCCUGAUGGGACAGGCCAGAUACAGUAUCCACAGAAGCACAGGGAUGCUCGUAUUGACAUAUAUUGGCACCUAAAAUGUCUACGAUUUUUUAUGGGUUAUCCAUCAGGAAACCUGGCUAUGCUCAUCUUAUAUGCGAAAAUGAAAAAGUUCACAUACAUCAUUCUGGAAGACAGUCUAGAAGGGAGGAUCCGGGCCCUUAUCAACAACUCAGGCAAUGCUACCUUCUAUGAUGAAAAUAGUGAUAUCUGGUUGAACCUGAGCUCCAACCUGGGCUACUACUUCCCCAAAGACAAACGCCAGAAGGCCUGGAACUGGUGGAAUCUGAACAUCCAUGUCCACGCACCCCCUGUCCAGCCCAUCUCCUUGAAAAUCAAUGAGUACAUCCAGGUACAAAUAAGGAGCCAGGAUAAGAUCAUCUUCUGCUUCACCUAUGAACAGAAGCAGAUUUGUUUAAACCUGGGCACCAGGUACAAGUUUGUGAUCCCAGAGGUGCUGAGCGAAAUGAAGAAGAAAACCAUCCUGGAGGCAGAACCCGGCCCAACAGCCCAGAAGAUCCGGGUCCUUCUGGGGAAAAUGAAUAGGCUCCUGAAUUACGCGACCACCCCUGAUCUGGAAAACUUCAUAGAGGCCGUCAGUAUAUCACUGAUGGACAACAAGUACCUGAAGAAGAUGCUCUCUAAACUCUGGUUUUAAGGCGGGGCUUAUCUGGCAUCCACCAAAUGCCUUAGGAAGUUGGAGACCUUGGGAGCUCCAGGGAAAAAAAACCCAAAGACCUGUUGACCUUUUAUGAGAGUUGGUUUGUAAUUUGGGACCUGUCGUGGCUCCUUGAUUUGAAGUAAACAUUUUUGGCAGAAGGGCUAA